GUAAUUUAUUAUGUUCUCCAGAAACUGAUUUUGCAACAUUGCUAAACUAGCAGACUGGAGAGAUGCUCACAAUUCUCAGAUGAUAUGAGUGUUUCUCUGCAUGGGCAUCAGAGCUGCCACUGCUUGACAUUCCAAGAACUUCCCAGCUACAGGUUCAUCACCUUCUCCUCCCAGGAAAGACAUGUGAGAUUCUGCACAGAGACAGGAAUGUCGCUGGGGGAUGCCAGCUGCCAUAUUGUGAAGACCCUCAAGCAUCCCUGUGGAGAGGUCCCCAUGGCACAGAAAUGGACUCUCAGCCCAAAAGCCAACAAAGAACCAAGGCCUCAAGCCAGCAGCCAUGGGAAUGGGAAUGUGCCAUCUUGGAAGCCAAUCCUGCAGCCCCAGUCAAGCCUUCAGAUGACAGUAGCCCCAGCCAAUAUCUUCACUGGAUCUUACUGAGAGACUAUGUGCCAGCAUGACCCUACUAAACAACUCUCAAAUUUCUGACCCUCAGAAAUUGUGUGAGAUAAUAAUUGUUUUUUGUUUUAAUAUGCUAAGCUUUAGGUUUGUUUGUUACUCCAAAUUAGACAACUAAUUCAGAAUGCAAUAUAUACACUCAGCCAGGUCAACUCCUCUGCUUCUUGAUGCCUGGGGAGAGUGGAGAGAGUGAUGGAUCCCCAUUAUUAUUGCACCCAGGGUACACUGGUCUGGGUUUAGAAUGUCUUGUGCUUUUUCAACCUUCUGUUCCCACAUUUCUCAGUAGUAUGUAUAUUAAACUCUCUUCAGUAACCCA